GAUAAACAAGCUCCUGUGGAAUUGUGGGUAGACACUGGACUUGUAAACGAAAAGCUUCAUAAGUCCCUCUUUGCUUAGUACUUUUCUCGUCCUUUCCCCAGGGUGCACGUAACCCUCAAGCACUAGGACCGUGCGGAAUCCAGGCUGCGAUGGCACCUUCAUUUACCGCCCGCAUUCAGUUGUUCCUCUUGCGGGCGCUAGGCUUUCUCAUAGGCUUAGUAGGCCGAGCAGCUUUAGUCUUAGGGGGUCCAAAGUUUGCCUCAAAGACCCCUCGGCCGGUGACUGAACCAUUGCUUCUGCUUUCGGGGAUGCAGCUGGCCAAGCUGAUCCGACAGAGAAAGGUGAAAUGUAUAGAUGUUGUUCAGGCUUAUAUCAACAGAAUCAAGGACGUGAACCCAAUGAUCAAUGGAAUUGUCAAGUACAGGUUUGAGGAAGCGAUGAAGGAGGCUCAUGCUGUAGAUCAAAAGCUUGCAGAGAAGCAGGAAGAUGAAGCCACCCUGGAAAAUAAAUGGCCCUUCCUUGGGGUUCCUUUGACAGUCAAGGAAGCUUUCCAGCUACAAGGAAUGCCCAAUUCUUCUGGACUCAUGAACCGUCGUGAUGCCAUUGCCAAAACAGAUGCCACUGUGGUGGCAUUACUGAAGGGAGCUGGUGCCAUUCCUCUUGGCAUAACCAACUGUAGUGAGUUGUGUAUGUGGUAUGAAUCCAGUAACAAGAUCUAUGGCCGAUCAAACAACCCAUAUGAUUUACAGCAUAUUGUAGGUGGAAGUUCUGGUGGUGAGGGCUGCACACUGGCAGCUGCCUGCUCAGUUAUUGGUGUGGGCUCUGAUAUUGGUGGUAGCAUUCGAAUGCCUGCUUUCUUCAAUGGUAUAUUUGGACACAAGCCUUCUCCAGGUGUGGUUCCCAACAAAGGUCAGUUUCCCUUGGCUGUGGGAGCCCAGGAGUUGUUUCUGUGCACUGGUCCUAUGUGCCGUUAUGCUGAAGACCUGGCCCCCAUGUUGAAGGUCAUGGCAGGACCUGGGAUCAAAAGGUUAAAACUAGACACAAAGGUACAUUUAAAAGACUUAAAAUUUUACUGGAUGGAACAUGAUGGAGGCUCAUUUUUAAUGUCCAAAGUGGACCAAGAUCUCAUUAUGACUCAGAAAAAGCUUAUUACGUGGAAGCAAUGGAAGACAAAGAAGGCCCUUACAUAAUGGUAAAGGGAUCAAUUCAACAAGAAGAGCUAACUACCCUAAAUAUAUAUGCACCCAAUACAGGAGCACCCAGAUUCAUAAAGCAAGUCCUUAGAGACCUACAAAGAGACAGACUCCCACACAAUAAUAAUGGGAGACUUUAACACGCCACUGUCAACAUUAGACAGAUCAAUGAGACAGAAAAUUAGCAAGGAUAUCCAGGAAUUGAAUUCAGCUCUGCACCAAGCAGACCUAAUAGACAUCUACAGAACUCUCCACCCCAAAUCAACAGAAUGUACAUUCUUCUCAGCACCAAACCACACCUAUUCCAAAAUUGACCACAUAGUUGGAUGUAAAGCACUCCUCAGCAAACGUAAAAGAACAGAAAUUAUAACAAACUGUCUCUCAGACCAUAGUGCAAACAAACUAGAACUCAGGAUUAAGAAACUCGCUCAAAACCGCUUAACUACAUGGAAACUGAACAACCUGCUCCUGAAUCACUACUGGGUACAUAACGAAAUGAAGGCAGAAAAAAAGAUGUUCUUUGAAACCAACGAGAACAAAGACACAACAUACCAGAAUCUCUGGGACACAUUUAAAGCAAUGUGUAGAGGGAAAUUUUUAGCACUAAAUGCCCACAAGAGAAAGCAGGAAUGAUCUAAAAUUGGCACUCUAACAUCACAAUUAAAAGAACUAGAGAAGCAAGAGCAAACACAUUCAAAAGCUAGCAGAAGGCAAGAAAUAACUAAGAUCAGAGAAGAACUGAAGGAGAUAGAGACAUAAAAAACCCUUCAUAAAAUCAAUGAAUCCAGAUGCUGGUUUUUUGACAAGAUCAACAAAAUUGAGAGACCGCUGGCAAGACUAAUAAAGAAGGAAAGAGAGAAGAAUCAAAUAGACGCAAUAAAAAAUUAUGAAGGGGAUAUCACCACCAAUCCCACAGAAGUACAAACUACCAUCACAGAAUACUAUAAACAUCUCUAUGCAAAUAAACUAGAAAAUCUAGAAGAAAUGGAUAAAUUCCUGGACACAUACACCCUCCCAAGACUAAACCAGGAAGAAGUUGAAUCUCUGAAUAGACCAAUAACAGGCUCUGAAACUGAGGCCAUAAUUAAUAGCCUAGCAACCAAAAAAAGUCCAGGAGCAGACAGAUUCACAGCCAAAUUCUACCAGAGGUACAAGGAGGAGCUGGUACCAUUCCUUCUGAAACUAUUCCAAUCAAUAGAAAAAGAGGGAAUCCUCCCUAACUCAUUUUAUGAGGCCAGCAUCAUCCUGAUACCAAAGCCUGGCAGAGACACAACCAAGAAAGAGAAUUUUAGGCCAAUAACCCUGAUGAACAUCGAUGCAAAAAUCCUAAAUAAAAUACUGCCAAACCGAAUCAAGCAACACAUCAAAAAGCUUAUCCACCAUGAUCAAGUGGGCUUCAUCCCUGGGAUGCAAGGCUGGUUUAACAUACGCAAAUCAAUAAACGUAAUCCAGCAUAUAAACAGAACCAAAGACAAAAACCACAUGAUUAUCUCAAUAGAUGCAGAAAAGGCCUUUGACAAAAUUUAACAACACUUCAAGCUAAAAGCUCUCAAUAAAUUAGGUAUUGAUGGGACGUAGCUCAAAAUAAUAAGAGCUAUCUAUGACAAACCCACAGCCAAUAUCAUACUGAAUGGCAAAAACUGGAAGCAUUCCCUUUGAAAACUGGCACAAGACAGCGAUGCUGUCUCUCACCACUCCUAUGCAACAUAGUGUUGGAAGUUCUGGUCAGGGAAAUCAGGCAGCAGAAGGAAAUAAAGGGUUUUCAACUAGAAAAGAGGAAGUCAAAUUGUCCCUGUUUGCUGAUGACAUGAUUGUAUAUCUAGAAAACUCCAUCUUCUCAGCCCAAAAUCUCCUUAAGCUGAGAAGCAACUUCAGCAAAGACUCAGGAUACAAAAUCAAUGUGCAAAAAUCACAAGCAUUCUUAUACACCAGUAACAGAAACAGAGAACCAAAUCAUGAGUGAACUCCCAUUCACAAUUGCUUCAAAGAGAAUAAAAUACCUGGGAAUCCAACUUGCAAGGGAUGUGAAGGACCUCUUCAAGGAGAACUACAAAUUACUGCUCAAUGAAAUAAAAGAGGAUACAAACAACUGGAAGAACAUUCCAUGCUCAUGGAUAGGAAAAAUCAAUAUCAUGAAAAUGGUCAUACUGCCCAAGGUAAUUUAUAGAUUCAAUGCCAUCCCUAUCAAGCUACCAAUGACUUUCUUCACAGAAUUGGAAAAAGCUACUUUGAAGUUCAUAUGGAACCAAAAAAGAGCCCACAUUGCCAAGUCAAUCCUAAACCAAAAGAACAAAGCUGGAGGCAUCAUGCUACCUGACUUCAAACUAUACUGGAAGACUACAGUAACCAAAACAGCAUGGUACUGGUACCAAAACAGAGAUAUAGCCCAAUGGAACAGAACAGAGCCCUCAGAAAUAAUGCCACACAUCUACAGCUAUCUGAUCUUUGACAAGCCUGACAAAAACAAGAAAUGGGGAAACAAUUCCCUAUUUAACAAAUGGUGCUGGGAAAACUGGCUAGCCAUAUGUAGAAAGCUGAAACUGGAUCCCUUCCUUACACCUUAUACAAAAAUUAAUUCAAGAUGGAUUAAAGACUUAAAUGUUAGACCUAAAACCAUAAAAACCCUAGAAGAAAACCUAGGCAAUACCAUUCAGGACAUAGGCAUGGGCAAGAACUUCAUGUCUAAAACACCAAAAGCAAUGGCAACAAAAGCCAAAAUUGACAAAUGGGAUCUAAUUAAACUCAAGAGCUUCUGCACAGCAAAAGAAACUACCAUCAGAGUGAACAGGCAACCUACAGAAUGGGAGAAAAUUUUUGCAAUCUACUCAUCUGACAAAGAGCUAACAUCCAGAAUCUACAAUGAACUCAAACAAAUUUACAAGAAAAAAACAAACAACCCCAUCAAAAAGUGGGCAAAGGAUAUGAACAGACACUUCUCAAAAGAAGACAUUUAUGCAGCCAAAAGACACAUGAAAAAAUACUCAUCAUCACUGGCCAUCAGAGAAAUGCAAAUCAAAACCACAAUGAGAUACCAUCUCACACCAGUUAGAAUGGCAAUCAUUAAAAAGUCAGGAAACAACAGGUGCUGGAGAGGAUGUGGAGAAAUAGGAACACUUUUACACUGUUGGUGAGACUGUAAACUAGUUCAACCAUUGUGGAAGUUAGUGUGGGGAUUCCUCAGGGAUCUAGAACUAGAAAUACCAUUUGACCCAGCCAUCCCAUUAGUGGGUAUAUACCCAUAAAGACACAUGCUAUUCACAAUAGCAAAGACUUGGAACCAACCCAAAUGUCCAACAAUGAUAGACUGGAUUAAGAAAAUGUGGCACAUAUACACCAUGGAAUACUAUGCAGCCAGAAAAAAUGAUGAGUUCAUGUCAUUUGUAGGGACAUGGAUGAAGCUGGAAACCAUUAUUCUCAGCAAACUAUCACAAGGACAGAAAACCAAAUACCGCAUGUUUUCACUCAUAGGUGGGAAUUGUACAAUGAGAAUACUUGGACACAGGAAGGGGAACAUCACACACCAGGGCCUGUUGUGGGGUGGGGGGAGUGGGGAAGGAUAGCAUUAGGAGAUAUACCUAAUGUGAAUGAUGAGUUAAUGGGUGCAGCACACCAACAUGGCACAUGUAUACAUAUGUAACAAACCUGCAUGUUGUGCACAUGUACCCUAAGACUUAAAGUAUAAUAAAAAAAAAAAAAAAAGACAUGUAAAACUAGAAGAAACUUGAUUGUGGUAAAAGAUGGCUUUUAUAUUCUAUCUUUGUUUUCUGCCACCAUGAAAAAAUGCCUGUGACUCAAUAACUUAUAAAGAAUAAAAAUUUAUUUCUCACACACCUGAAGACAGGAAAGUCCAAGAUCAAGGUUCUGGCAGGUUCAGUGUCUGGUGAGGGCCAUCUUACUGCCUUCUCCAGAGGGGAGAAACAUGGCAGAAGGGUGGAAGAGACAGCUGCUAAGGCUGCAUAAAGCCUUUGUAAAAAUGGCUGUAAUGGCAUUAACUAGGGCAGCCCUCAUGGCCUAAUCACUUCUUUAGGGCCCCCCUCUUAAUAAUAAUGCAUUAGCAACACCUGAAUUUUGGAGGCGAUCUAUUCAAACCAUAGGUCAGGACAUCCAGGCCAUCCUGGCUAACACGGUGAAAUCCCGUCUCUACUAAACAAAAUACAAAAAAUUAGCCGGGCGCGGUGGCGGGCGCCUGUAGUCCCAGCUACUCGGGAGGCUGAGGCAGGAGAAUGGCGUCAACCCGGGAGGCGGAGCUUGCAGUGAGUGAAGAUCGCACCACUGCACUCCAGCCUGGGCGACAGAGUGAGACUCCGUUAAAAAAAAAAAAAAAUAGCAUAAGUGGAUACAUUACUGUGUUACUAGAUUUGAAAGUCAUGUUAUAAAAUUAUACGUUAUUUUUAAAUCUAUAGGGAAAAUGUAAUUCAUAUAAAAACUCAGUGGAUUUUUAAAUUUCUUUUUGUAAUGCUUAAUGAGGAUAAAAGAAAAGUGAGAUCUUCAUAAGUUAUAAGCCCAGAAACAGAAUUUCUUCCUAUAUUAAUUUUUACGUGUAUUAAGAUAGCUUCACAUAUCUGAAUUAAUAAUAUCUAAAUGAAAGAAAUCAUAGAAAAUACUGCCAAUAAAAAUGAUAGAGGAUUAUUAACAGGCUAUAACCUAUUAUAAGAGAAAUACCACCAGGGACAUAGGUAAAGGAGAAAGGUAAAUUAUAAAAGAAGUUAUAUAAGUGAACAAUAAAAACACAAGAAAUGUUAAGACUUAUAAGUAAUUAAAGGAAAAACUAUAGAAAAAUUAAGGUACUAUACCUUCGUUGCUUGGGUUGAUAAACCAUAGAAUGCUAGUGGCAAAGCAAAUUGGUACUUUCCUGGCGAGCUGGAGGAUAAAUGCAAAAUUAUGAAGCCAGGAGCAGGAGGAAAAAAGUAAGUGAAUGGAAGUAAAUUACUUACAUUGAACUUUUAGUCCAAUGUAAUUUGCUCUCACAGUAGAAUUACCUCCCUUCCUGUUCUGUAGCUUUAGCAAAAAUUCUAAUAACUUAAUGUACAGACUCUUCAUUACCAAAUUCUCUAGCCAAUUUAAUAUUCUGACCCCAAACCCUUCCCUUUACGGUAUUAAAACCAUAUUUUUGCUGGCCUGAAAUUCAUGUGUAUGAAAAGCCAAUUUUCCUAAAUGGGUUUUUUCACUGUUGAUACUAAUCAAGAGUCUCACUGUUAUUGAAACUUUCUCUGCAGUGUCAGAAGUGACAGUGUUGCAGACCUCAUCACCUGUUGGCAUCAGGUAGCAGGGAGAGCUAUCACAGAAUAGUUUAGUUUGAAAUAAUAGUUUAAAAUAGUCACAUGCUAAAAAAGAGACAGAUUGAAAUACAUGUGAAUUCAUUUAGGAGUUUCAUUUCAUAUUGGAUAAGUUUAGAACAGGCUCUAGUGAAGAUUGGUGUAUGGAAUACAAGGAUCUAUACUACUGUUGUAUGCUUUACAAGUUGGUUCCAUAAGAGAAAUUUUAUAACCUAAAUAUUUUUCCAGAAAGCAUUUUAUAAAAUUCAGAUGUCUGUUUCUGAUUAAAAAUUAUUUUUUGCCAUACUAUGUUCUUUUUAUAUUAUAUGCAUGAAAUCCAGGGCAAUCUCUUUAAAAUAUAAAGUUAGAUAAGCAUGCUAACCAUCACCAUUAUUAUUUAUAGAAAGUAUGCCAAGGAUAAAUUAGAAAUAAGAGGUAUGACUAUGAAAAAAGACAAAUCAAUAAUUAUUUAUAGAUUAAGAUAUGAGUAUAUUCUUGUAAAACUCAAGGAGUGCUAUUUUAAAACUCUUAGAAUAAAUGAGUUCAACCUAAAAUAGGAUGUACGAUGAAAAUGAGAAAAACCAUAGCUAACAUAUCAGCAAUAACCAGAUAAAAAGUAGAAUGAGGAAAACAGAGAAGACAAACAGAAAAUCCUACAAAAUGCCUACAGACUCUAAAAAUAAGGUUGUAGAACCUACCAGAGAAAAAUUACAGAACUUUACUAAGAGUCCUAAAAUGAGUUUUGAAUAAAAAAAGAAACUUAGUUUUAUAGCUUGAGUUGUUGGUGGAUAGAUCCCAUAGCCUAUAUAAUCCCUGUCACUGGGAUUACAAAUAUCAUUCCAUUUUAUAAAGUUCCUAGGCACACUCCAAAAUUCCAUCACAGUGAUAAAUGCAUUUCUGAAACACCAACAGGCCUGCUGUUCUAUAAUCUGUCAUUGCAUAAAUUAAUUUAUGUAUCUUUGUUUCUGUAUAUUUUCUGAAAAGGAGGAAGUGGAGGAACAUGAGAAUGAGUGAUGUGUGUAUCUGAGGAGGGAGGAGGUAAAUAGAGAAAGACAUUAUUACAUCAUUGGAGGUGGGGUAAGGAUGUGUGCCACCUCCACCAUUCCCAAGCUAUUGUCAGAAAAAUACCAUGUUUUAGGACAGGAUGGCUAUAUUUUAUAGCAAUUAAAAUCAAAUUAGCAACUUUUAUUAUGGAAGUUGAGAAAAUGAUGUUAAGGUUCUCCUGUCAGAAUAAAUAGCCAAGAAGAAAUGAAAACUUUUGACUCAGGAGAAUAAAAAUAUUAAGGAUUUAGUAUUCCAGAAUUUUAAUAUGGCAUAAUACAUUUAAAUAUUUCUCUAAAGUUAAUAACUUUAUAUAGCAAUUUGAACUUUAUCCACUUUCAGGUUCAAUAUAAAGAGGGAGCUUUUUUGAUUUUGUAGCAGAAACUCAAUAGUUGCUAACUGAUGUUGGUCUGUAAUUCUUUCUAAGUCAGAAUAAAAGGAAAGGAGUUAGGACAUCAAACUUUGUGGGGGAUAUUUUAUAAUCCAGGUCUUUUUAUCAUUUCUAUAUUUCCUAGCAACACCUUACUUUUACCUAUUUUGUAGAAAAAUAUGCCAAGGCCUUGUGUGCUGUUGGAUUUUUUUAUUAGCAGAUUUUAUUUUUAGAACAGUUAUAUAUUUACCAAAAGAUUGAGCAGAUAGUACAGUGUCCAUGGGUAGCCCCUCUUUCUUUCACUAGUAGGGUACAUGUUUCAUGACUGAUGAAACAAUAUUGAUAUAUUAUUAACUAAACUCCAUAGUUUACAUUAGUGUUUAUAUUGUACAGUUUUACAGCAUUUGACAAAUGCAUAAUGCCAUGUAACUAUCAUUACAAUAUCAUACAGAAUAGUAGUUUUUACCACUCAAAAAACUUCUGUGCAUCACUUAUUUAUUCAUACAUUCUCUCCACUCCUACUGGAAACCACAGAUUUUUUACUGUCUUUAUACUUUUGCCUUUCCCCUAAUAUCAUAUAUUUAGAAUCUAAAUUAUGUAACCGUUUUAUACUUGCUUCUUUCACAUUGAAAUACGCAUUUAAGUUCCCUCCAUGUCUUUUCGUGGCUUGGUAACUCUUUUUAUCUCUGAAUAAUAUUUCAUUUUAAGGAUGUGCCACCAUUUUUUACCUAUUUACCUAGUAAAGGACAUCUUGGUUGUUUCAAAAUAUUGUUAUCUUUGAACAAAAGCUGUUAUAAUCAUUUAUGUGCACCUUUUCCAUAGACAUGUUUUCUAUUCAAUUAGGUAGUACCAAGGAACACAAUAUACUUUGCUUUGUUAGAAAUCUUGAGAUUGUCUUCCAAAGUGGGUUUGUUAUGGUACUCCAGAGAAGCAGAAGAAAUUCCUUCUGCUUCUCUGGAGUACCCUAAUUUUAGUACCCUUACACACACACAUACACACGCACACACACACACACCUACACACACACACACAUAUAUAUAUAUACAUAUAUAAUAUAUAAUGACUAAUACAAAUGAAAGUUUGUACCCUCUGACCAAUAUAGCUUUAUUUCAUCCCCUUACCCCACCCCAAUUCCUGGCAACUACGAUUCUACUCUCUACUUCUAGGAAUUUGACUUUUUUAGAUUACAUAAAUAAAUGAUAUUAUAAAACA